ACUGCUGUGCAGGGCAGGAAAGCUCCACACACACAGCCCAGCAAACAGCAGCACGCUGCUGAAAAAAAGACUCAGAGGAGAGAGAUAAGGAAGGAAAGUAGUGAUGGAUCUCAUCCCAAACUUGGCCGUGGAAACCUGGCUUCUCCUGGCUGUCAGCCUGAUACUCCUCUAUCUAUAUGGAACCCGUACACAUGGACUUUUUAAGAAGCUUGGAAUUCCAGGGCCCACACCUCUGCCUUUUUUGGGAAAUGCUUUGUCCUUCCGUAAGGGCUAUUGGACGUUUGACAUGGAAUGUUAUAAAAAGUAUAGAAAAGUCUGGGGUAUUUAUGACUGUCAACAGCCUAUGCUGGCUAUCACAGAUCCCGACAUGAUCAAAACAGUGCUAGUGAAAGAAUGUUAUUCUGUCUUCACAAACCGGAGGCCUUUCGGGCCAGUGGGAUUUAUGAAAAAUGCCAUCUCUAUAGCUGAGGAUGAAGAAUGGAAGAGAAUACGAUCAUUGCUGUCUCCAACAUUCACCAGCGGAAAACUCAAGGAGAUGGUCCCUAUCAUUGCCCAGUAUGGAGAUGUGUUGGUGAGAAAUCUGAGGCGGGAAGCAGAGACAGGCAAGCCUGUCACCUUGAAACACGUCUUUGGGGCCUACAGCAUGGAUGUGAUCACUAGCACAUCAUUUGGAGUGAGCAUCGACUCUCUCAACAAUCCACAAGACCCCUUUGUGGAAAACACCAAGAAGCUUUUAAGAUUUAAUCCAUUAGAUCCAUUCGUUCUCUCAAUAAAAGUCUUUCCAUUCCUUACCCCAAUUCUUGAAGCAUUAAAUAUCACUGUGUUUCCAAGAAAAGUUAUAAGUUUUCUAACAAAAUCUGUAAAACAGAUAAAAGAAGGUCGCCUCAAAGAGACACAAAAGCACCGAGUGGAUUUCCUUCAGCUGAUGAUUGACUCUCAGAAUUCAAAAGACUCUGAGACCCACAAAGCUCUGUCUGAUCUGGAGCUCAUGGCCCAAUCAAUUAUCUUUAUUUUUGCUGGCUAUGAAACCACGAGCAGUGUUCUCUCCUUCAUUAUAUAUGAACUGGCCACUCACCCUGAUGUCCAGCAGAAAGUGCAGAAGGAAAUUGAUACAGUUUUACCCAAUAAGGCACCACCCACCUAUGAUACUGUGCUACAGUUGGAGUAUCUUGACAUGGUGGUGAAUGAAACACUCAGAUUAUUCCCAGUUGCUAUGAGACUUGAGAGGGUCUGCAAAAAAGAUGUUGAAAUCAAUGGGAUGUUUAUUCCCAAAGGGGUGGUGGUGAUGAUUCCAAGCUAUGUUCUUCAUCAUGACCCAAAGUACUGGACAGAGCCUGAGAAGUUCCUCCCUGAAAGGUUCAGUAAAAAGAACAAGGACAACAUAGAUCCUUACAUAUACACACCCUUUGGAAGUGGACCCAGAAACUGCAUUGGCAUGAGGUUUGCUCUCGUGAACAUGAAACUUGCUCUAGUCAGAGUCCUUCAGAACUUCUCCUUCAAACCUUGUAAAGAAACACAGAUCCCCCUGAAAUUACGCUUUGGAGGACUUCUUCUAACAGAAAAACCCAUUGUUCUAAAGGCUGAGUCAAGGGAUGAGACCUUUGUAGAUAUGGAGCCCAUUCACAUGGACUUUUUAAGAAGCUUGGCAUUCCAGGGCCCACACCUCUGCUUUUUUUGGGAACUACUUUGUCCUACCAUCAGAUCCCGCUGAAAUUACGCUUAGGAGGACUUCUUCAACCAGAAAAACCCAUUGUUCUAAAGGUUGAGUCAAGGGAUGGGACCGUAAGUGGAACCUGAAUUUCCCUAAGGACUUCUGCUUUGCUCUUCAAAAAAGCUGUGACCUAGAACACCAGAGACCUCAAAUUACUUUGUGAAUAGUACCCUGAAAUGAAGAUGGGCUUCAUCCACUGUACUGCAUAAAUAACCAGGGAUUCUGUACAUGCACUGAGCUCUCUCCCUGUCUGUGUAGAGUGUUAUACUUGGGAAUAUAAAGGAAGUGACCAAAUCAGUGCUUGGGAAGUAGAUUUGGCUUCUUUGUUUCUCACAGGACAAUCUCAGCCACCCCUAGUUAGCACCAUUAACUCCUCCUGAGCUCUGAUAAAAGAAUCAAAAUUUCUCAAUAAUUUCAUCCAAAAUUAUUAAUGAAAAUAAGAAUUAUUUUGAUGGCUCUAACAGUGACAUUUAUAUCAUCUGUUUUAUCUGGAGCAUUCUAUAAUAAGUUUAUAUUAAGCAAAUCAAUAAAAACCUCUUACAAAAGUAU